AAUGAAAGUGAAAGAGGGGUGGGGCGGGGGCGAGCCCGGGUUCUGUGGCCCAUUUGCCCUGUGGCCUUGAGCAAGCCCCUCCCCCAGGCCUCGGGGGCUCUCCCGGUUUGGGGGAACCGGGCGAGGCAAUGCCACAGGCCCAGGGUUAGAGGGGGUGGGCACUUGCAGCUGCCGAUGUGGCUGGAUCUGGAACUUCUCAGACGGCUCCUGUCAGCGCCAAGUUUCACCAAAUCCAGGCCUGCGGGCUCCUCCCCCAGGACCCCCACUCGCAGUCCCUCAAGCCUGUGCUCCCGGAAAGGCACUGGGCGACCGCACCCGUGGCUUUCUCUGGGCGACCGGGUCCCAGACUCCCCCCAGCACAGCAGAGCGCUUCCCUGCCCACCCGCGGAAACCGCCCCAGGAUGCAGCACCGAGGCUUCCUCCUCCUCACCCUCCUCGCCCUGCUGGCGCUCACCUCCGCGGUCGCCAAAAAGAAAGAUAAGGUGAAGAAGGGCGGCCCGGGGAGCGAGUGCGCUGAGUGGGCCUGGGGGCCCUGCACCCCCAGCAGCAAGGAUUGCGGCGUGGGUUUCCGCGAGGGCACCUGCGGGGCCCAGACCCAGCGCAUCCGGUGCAGGGUGCCCUGCAACUGGAAGAAGGAGUUUGGAGCCGACUGCAAGUACAAGUUUGAGAACUGGGGUGCGUGUGAUGGGGGCACAGGCACCAAAGUCCGCCAAGGCACCCUGAAGAAGGCGCGCUACAAUGCUCAGUGCCAGGAGACCAUCCGCGUCACCAAGCCCUGCACCCCCAAGACCAAAGCAAAGGCCAAAGCCAAGAAAGGGAAGGGAAAGGACUAGACGCCAAGCCUGGAUGCCAAGGAGCCCCUGGUGUCACAUGGGGCCUGGCCCACGCCCUCCCUCUCCCAGGCCCGAGAUGUGACCCACCAGUGCCUUCUGUCUGCUCGUUAGCUUUAAUCAAUCAUGCCCUGCCUUGUCCCUCUCACUCCCCAGCCCCACCCCUAAGUGCCCAAAGUGGGGAGGGACAAGGGAUUCUGGGAAGCUUGAGCCUCCCCCAAAGCAAUGUGAGUCCCAGAGCCCGCUUUUGUUCUUCCCCACAAUUCCAUUACUAAGAAACACAUCAAAUAAACUGACUUUUUCCCCCCAAUAAAAGCUCUUCUUUUUUAAUAUAUAAAAGCCCCUU